CCUUUUCUUCGGAGUUUCCUGUUUGUGACGGAAAAAGUGCAAGUAUGAAGGAUUAAGUCUCGUUUAAUUAAUCUUGUAGGGAAUUUUGAGGUAGUGGGUCGAUUUACUUUUGGUUCUAAGUCUUUUCACAUUAAACAACAUCGAAUUAAAGCACAGAAUAACAGAUUCUUUUCAUAUUUCACUUGAUGUUUGGGUAAUGUUUGCAUCCAUUUGUUGCACUCUACUAGGACAUAUGGCAGAUGGUAUUCUUAAAGCUGAUGUAACUGCGAGGGCCUAAUGGGUUAUUUAUGGUAGUGUUAACAGUAAGGAGUGGGUUUUGAGUAUUAACAACUUAGGGAAAGCUUUCUAUUGCACAAGAGCUGUGCUAACUUGCUUAAAUAUCUUCUCUUCAAUUGGGUGUGCUGGAGGUCUAGGUUGUCCAGGUUAUAUACUCUACUUGGAGAAGUUGUUAACAGUGAAGCCUUGAAUCAGCUCAGAACUUGUUAUACUUUCAGAUGGAUUCAGUGUCCUGUAACAUUCUUUUUCCCCCCCGCCCCAUGUGAUCUGCAGGAAACUAACAUUCUUGACUUGGAAUAGAACUAAAAUAAAUUUAGGAUAAAUAGUAACAAAGGAUUGCAUCAUUUUGUACGUUUGACAAUAAGUUUAAAAAUCCAUUAGAUGCAAAAAUCUGUCCAAAGUUACUAGUCUUAAUACUUUUUUUACUCAAUGGGUAGUUUAUGAAAUUUGGAUCUUGGACUGUUGUGCCUUAUUUCCUAAGUGCAUUUAAAUUGUGUAGGUUCUUCCUCGAUGUUGAAAAAGGAAAAAAAAUUGGGUAGGUUCUUUGGGCAGUGAUUGUGUAUAAGUGAAGUCUUAAUGCUGUAAUGGCUUUUCUUAUCUGCAAACCUAGGCCAUUCUUGUGGUUGUUGUAUUUCAAGUUAAAAGGGUACACUUUUCAGUAGUUUAUUUUCACCUAACAGCCAUUAUGUGUGCAAUUGGUAGUGUAGAAAACAAAAAGGUAUUGGGAGAGUAGUCGGUGGGUUUGGCCAGAAUGUGUUUUGAUCAGGCAGAACAAAGGUAUAAAAAAAAGUGUUUUGAGAAACUGCCCUGAUUUCAGAAAUUAGCCAUCAUUUUUUAAUCUACAUUGGAUUUUUAAAGUUGUUCUUUUUUUCUUUUUAAAGCGGGGAGAGUCUCAUUUACCCAGGCUGGUCUUGAACUUGCUUCAAGUCAUCCUCCCGCUUCAGCCCCCCGAGUAGCUGGCCUUACAGACUUGAGCCACUGUGUCAGGAUGGAUUUUUGAAAUUUGAAAGUCAUAUUUUCAUGAGCAAAUUCGAUUAAAGAAUAUCAGAAAAGUAUAUGGAAGGUGUAUGUGGUAUCGUUUACGGUUAUUAAAACCCCAGCCAAAUAUUAUUCCUACAGUAAAGAAAAUAGUUCUGCUUGCAGGAUGGGCAUUGUUCUUAUUCCUUGCAUAUAAAGUUUCCAAAACAGACCGAGAAUACCAAGAAUACAAUCCUUAUGAAGUAUUAAAUUUGGAUCCUGGAGCCACAGUAGCAGAAAUUAAAAAACAAUAUCGUUUGCUGUCACUUAAAUAUCAUCCAGAUAAAGGAGGUGAUGAGGUUAUGUUCAUGAGGAUAGCAAAAGCUUAUGCUGCUUUAACGGAUGAAGAGUCCCGGAAAAAUUGGGAAGAAUUUGGAAAUCCAGAUGGGCCUCAAGCCACAAGCUUUGGAAUUGCCCUGCCAGCUUGGAUAGUUGACCAGAAAAACUCAAUUCUGGUUUUACUUGUAUAUGGAUUGGCAUUUAUGGUUAUCCUUCCAGUUGUUGUGGGCUCUUGGUGGUAUCGCUCAAUACGCUAUAGUGGAGACCAGAUUCUAAUACGCACAACACAGAUUUAUACAUACUUUGUUUAUAAAACCCGAAAUAUGGAUAUGAAACGUCUUAUCAUGGUUUUGGCUGGAGCUUCUGAAUUUGAUCCUCAGUAUAAUAAAGAUGCCACAAGCAGACCAACGGAUAAUAUUCUAAUACCACAGCUAAUCAGAGAAAUUGGCAGCAUUAAUUUAAAGAAGAAUGAGCCUCCACUUACCUGCCCAUAUAGCCUGAAGGCCAGAGUUCUUUUACUGUCUCAUCUUGCUAGAAUGAAAAUUCCUGAGACCCUUGAAGAAGAUCAGCAAUUCAUGCUAAAAAAGUGUCCUGCCCUACUUCAAGAAAUGGUUAAUGUAAUCUGCCAACUAAUAGUAAUGGCCCGGAACCGUGAAGAAAGGGAGUUUCGUGCUCCAACUUUGGCAUCCCUAGAAAACUGCAUGAAGCUUUCUCAGAUGGCCGUUCAGGGACUUCAGCAAUUUAAGUCUCCCCUUCUGCAGCUCCCUCAUAUUGAAGAGGACAAUCUUAGACGGGUUUCUAAUCAUAAGAAGUAUAAAAUUAAAACUAUCCAGGAUUUGGUGAGUUUAAAAGAAUCAGAUCGUCACACUCUACUGCACUUCCUUGAAGAUGAAAAAUAUGAAGAGGUUAUGGCUGUCCUUGGGAGUUUUCCAUAUGUGACCAUGGAUAUAAAAUCACAGGUGUUAGAUGAUGAAGAUAGCAACAACAUCACAGUAGGAUCCUUAGUUACAGUGUUGGUUAAGUUGACAAGGCAAACAAUGGCUGAAGUAUUUGAAAAGGAGCAGUCCAUCUGUGCUGCAGAGGAACAGCCAGCAGAAGAUGGGCAGGGUGAAACUAACAAGAACAGGACAAAAGGAGGAUGGCAACAGAAGAGUAAAGGACCCAAGAAAACUGCUAAAUCAAAAAAAAAGAAACCUUUAAAAAAAAAACCUACACCUGUGCUAUUACCACAGUCAAAGCAACAGAAACAAAAGCAGGCAAAUGGAGUCGUUGGGAAUGAAGCUGCAGUAAAGGAAGAUGAAGAAGAAGUUUCAGAUAAGGGCAGUGAUUCUGAAGAAGAAGAAACCAAUAGAGAUUCCCAAAGUGAGAAAGAUGAUGGUAGUGACAGAGACUCUGAUAGAGAGCAAGAUGAAAAACAAAACAAAGAUGAUGAAGCAGAGUGGCAAGAAUUACAACAAAGCAUACAGCGAAAAGAGAGAGCUCUAUUGGAAACCAAAUCAAAAAUAACACAUCCUGUGUAUAGCCUUUACUUUCCUGAGGAAAAACAAGAAUGGUGGUGGCUUUACAUUGCAGAUAGGAAGGAGCAGACAUUAAUAUCCAUGCCAUAUCAUGUGUGUACGCUGAAAGAUACAGAGGAGGUAGAGCUGAAGUUUCCUGCACCAGGCAAGCCUGGAAAUUAUCAGUAUACUGUGUUUCUGAGAUCAGACUCCUAUAUGGGUUUGGAUCAGAUUAAACCAUUGAAGUUGGAAGUUCAUGAGGCUAAGCCUGUGCCAGAAAAUCACCCACAGUGGGAUACAGCAAUAGAGGGGGAUGAAGACCAGGAGGACAGUGAGGGCUUUGAAGAUAGCUUUGAGGAAGAAGAGGAGGAAGAAGAAGAUGAUGACUAAGCAGUACUCUGAAUGGACCACAGUGUUUGCACAUAUUUGCAAUUUUUUGCUGUUUUGGAAGUGUAUCAUAAACCAGAAACAGUACAGAACUGAUGUUGAGGGAGGUGUAGUUUUUUUACUCUUGAAAUGGGUGCAUAAUAUAACUAGGCAGUGGCGGUGCCUUGGUACAACCUGAAAAAUGUUAAGGCUUAUUGAAACCUUUCAAGUAGGGGAUGGUACAUUUAUUUCAUCUGCAAAUGAUAAUAAAUCCUUUGUUAUUAUAACUGUCCAGAAGUGUGGGCUAUGUAUUAUCUGAUCAGUCUAUGGUCCCAGUAAAAGUAAAGAUGCAGGAAACACAGUCUGUAAAUGAGCGACUUUUCUUUGUUCAGCUUUAGUUUUAGCAAACACCACAAAUAUGUUUUAAGUAACAUCGCUCAAGUUUAAGUAACAUCGCUCAAGUUGAUAAUCUCUUGAUAAGCUCUGUUGUUGACAUUUUGCAGUGAUACAACAGCUCCACUCAUAGAUUUAAACUUUUAUUUUUACUUAUCUUGGUCAUAAGUUGGCAUUCUCUCACAUUCCACAUGAUAUAGAGGGCUACGUUUUGGAAUUUUCCUUUUCUUAAUUGCCCAGAGUUAUCAGACAGAUUAUAAAAAUGGCUUUUAAUGGCUUAAACCAUUUCUAAACCUCUAUCUUAGCAGAUCAAUGCAGGAUCUAAUUCUUUUGAUAAGUUCUAGCUCUAAAAGUGAUAGUGGGACUGUAUGUUUUCUGAUACUGGUGGCUUAUGUUAUUAAACCUUUUUUAAAAAAGGUUCACUCUAAAAGCUGAACUACAUCCUUAGUUUUCAGUCUACUUGACUCUAUCAGGAGCUUUUUAAGGAAAGUAAGUAUAACAUGCAAAGGAAGCUUUUUUUGUAUUCAUUUUGGACUCCUGUCAAUAAAAAUAGAAGUUUGUUGACUCGUUUUAUGUUUCAAUGGUGUGUGUCUUUUUACUAUCAGGACAUAAAUAGGGCAAUCCACUUCUUUAUUUUUCAACUAAAGAUUGAAUAGUAUUGUACAUUACUGCUAAAGUGACUGCUAUUUCUGUAUACUGUAGAAAAACCCAGGAGUGAGAGGGAUUUCCCCUCAUAGUACAACUGGAAGGAUAGUGCUUGUAAAGAGUAGAGAUGUGUACAUGAUGAAUCAUUGAGGGAGGGUGGAUAUUUUUAUUCCUAGAUAUGGAGGAAACAUAAGUCUGUAGUAUUAUAAAACUGAUUGUAAUAAUUCUUUCCUAUCAAAAUCUCCAUAGGUCAAAAUAUUGUUGGAAUACUAAAAUUUGCAACCUUGUUUACUUUAAAAGGUUGCCACUUUCAGUGCAGAAUACUACCGGCAUCUUGUUACUGCAAUAGUUGGAAAUAAAAUGUGAAAAUUAGCAAAACCAUGAAUGGUUUUUUUGGUUCUAAAUUUAAGAUGUAAUAUUUCCUAUAAAAGGGUGAAAGCAGUUUCUUUCUCUAUAACCUCAAUCACCAGUUUAGUGAGAGCCUUUCUUGGCAGGCAGGAGGCAGUGUCACUGAGGAUUUUUUUCAUUUACUUCAUUGUACAAGUAGGAGGGUGGGUUUAAUUUUCAAAUCAGGUUCUGCUGUGAAGCACCAGUGUCUUGAGGCAGCUACUGAUUACCUAAGUGUGGUGGCAGGGGGUAAGCCAGCUGGUGUCAAGUGAAAGGAGGGAUUAGAGAAAACAGGUGUGGCACGAAGGCAAGGAAACUGAGCAGACAAGACAGAACAAUGUGUAGAAUGCAUAUUUCCUAGUUUUCUUGAAAGAUUUCAAGAAAAGUUGUUUUUUUUUUUCUAGUGGCUACUUUGCCUUAAAGAGGCUUUAUAAGUUCAUUCACACAGCUGGCUUCUCUGGUUUUAAGAUUCUGGAGAGGAUGAUAACCUAGUAACACCACAGUGCUUAAAAAAAAAAAAAAAAAAAAAACUACCAUCACCAGAAAAUUCCACCAGUUUGUUUUCCUUUUCUCUUUGUGUGAUGUGUAUGUACUUCCCAACUAAGUAAAAUAAAAUUUCCUCUAGUGAGUGCUUUAGGUAACCUCUUUCCAUAUGGCAGUAGUGAAAGAACUGAGCCUUCAGUUGAUAGUUCUUCUCUCUCCAGCAAGUCGCUAAACUCCACAUCCCUUCGUUUUUCCUCUGGAAUGAGAAUAACAAACUAUCCUAGUUUGCAUUUAAUCUAAUGGAAACUUGAGCAAAGUUUCAAUUUUCUUCCUAUAAAGAAACUGACAUUUUGUCAACAAUUGAUGAGCCUAUAGAUCAUACAGUGUAUAGGAAGUGAAAUUGAAACAGUUAAAUUAUGUGAUAUUUUUCUCUAAUUGGUAAAGUACCUAUUAAAAUACAGCUGUUCAUGAGGAGACUUACCACAAUUCAAAGUGUAGCAGUUGUGUAUUUUAGCAUUAUAAUAUUUGAUUGAGGCCCUGAGGUGUUAAUAUCUCAAUCUCAGAGUUAGAUGUUCAUGUCCUUUUUGAAUUUUUUAAACAUUUUUCAUAAUUUUUUUUUUAAGUUAGGGAGCACAUUGAGUGAAGUUCUCUGUGUAGAACAAUACCUUCUGCUCUGCUUCUCCCAGCUUUCACUGAGGGCUGGAAAAGGACAGGCCUGUCCAGCUGUACUGUCCCACUGUGUAUGGGGAAGCUCAGGCUCUGGUGGAAGCAGGGGGCGUGGAUGUCAAACAACUGAUGUGGAAACAGGGAGGGAGAGAUAUAAUGAGGCUCUCUAGGCAUGUUAUUUUUGACCACAAGUUUUGUUCAGUUUGCUUCAGCCAAUCCAAACCAUAUACUAGAGUGUUCUGUAGUCACAAUUCUUAUUUCAAAUGUAAUUCAGCACCUUACAUAAUUUUUGAGAGGUUGUCAUUCAUCACAUAUUUACUGAGUUUCUAUGUGCCAGGCUCUGUGACUGGAUACUGGAGCUAUCAAAAUGAAAAAAAUAGUGUUAAGAACUCACUCGCUGGUGUUAGAGCAGGUAGAUGAGUGGCAAUCCAUUUAAAUCCAUUUGCCUUGGCUAUUAUUUGGAAUGCCUUUUUUUUUUUUUAGUCUAUCUACUGUAGGCAGAAGAAUUAUUUCUUUAGGGGCUAGCUGUUUAUUUUGCUGGCCUUUUUUUCUCUCUUUCUCUUUUUCUUCUUAAGACGGAGUCUCGCUCUGUCCUCCAGGCUGGAGGAGUGCAGUGGCACGAUCUCAGCUCACUGCAACCUCCGCCUCCCAGCUUCAAGCGAUUCUUCUGCCUCAGCCUCCUGAGUAGCUGGGACUGCAGGUGCAUGCCACCACACCCAGCUAAUUUUUUAAUUUUUAGUAGAGAUGGGAUUUUGCCACGUUGUCCAGCCUGGUCUCGAACUCCUGGCCUCAAGUGAUCAGCCCUCCUCAGCCUCCCAAAGUGCUGGCAUUACAGGCAUGAGCCACUGCGCCCAGCCUGUUGGGUUUUUUUGGAAAAAAAACAAAAACAACAAAUCAUCAUCCUUUCCUUUAAAAUGUUUUUUUUUUUUUAAGAAACAAUUUUCCCACAAACGGUCUGAUUUAACUCCAUGAAAUCCUCUAUUUAGACUGCCUUAAAGUGAAAUAACUGUUGGUGAACCAUAACAUUUUGCCAGCUGUGUAGUGAUUAGUCCAAAUAUGUCUCAAGAAGUUAGCACCAAGCAUUCUCAUCCAUUUAAACUUGAUGCUAGGGCUAUUUUGCAAAACUUAAAAAGAUGCGAUCUUGUACAUAUUUCUGUAACCUGAGCUGAAAACCCAAAUAACAAUCAUUGACAUACUUUAGGGCUAUUGUUUCAGGUGGGGGUGUAUACAUCCCAGGGGCGUGGAGAUGAUCAAUCCAUUGAGGAAGUAUUAAGAUGAUUAUUUGUAUUUAAUCUCAUCCUUUUAAAUUUCUAUUUUUGUGUGUUUUAUAAUGUACAUAAUAUAUUGUACAAUUGUACACUUCUAUUAUUUAUAAAUAAACAUUUAUUGGUGCAUUAA